CUGAUGUCAUUGAUUUUGUAAAUGUGUGUCGAUUUUAGAAAUGUACUGAUGCUGUUGGUACAAGGAAGUUUAUAUCUGAUUUAUGUUUGUUCAUAGUUAAGUGUAAUAUGUUAUAAGCAAUGUUUAAGUCAACUCUGGAAUUCACAGGAUUCUUUUUUUUUUUUUUUUUGGAGACGGAGUCUCACUCUGUCACCCUGGCUGGAGUGCAGUGGUGUGAUCUCAGCUCACUGCAACCUUUGCCUCCCGGGUUCAAGCAAUUCUCCUGCCUCAGCCUCCCGAGUAGCUGGGAUUACAGACAUGCACUACCACACCCGGCUAAUUUUUGUAUUUUUAGUACAGAUAGUACUGUGUUGGCCAUGCUGGUCUCGAACUCCUGGACUCAGGUGAUCCGCCUUCCUCGGCCUCCCAAAGUGUUGGGAUGACAGGCGUGAGCCACUGCACACAGCCUCACAGGAGUCUUUAAUAAGGUCUACAUGUUAAUCAAGUAUGAGAAAUAUUCUAAUGGGACUUGAAAUCCUCAAGAACUAUAUAGGACGGAAAACAUAAGUGUUUCAUUUCUCAAUGUGUAUUUAUCUCCUCUGUCAUUUAAAUUGAGGGCAUAACACUAUGGAAAAAGUAAAUGUUAAAUCUCCCAAUCCUAAACAAGGAACGUCUGUGUUAUUUUCCCACAGAAGAAACUCUUCUCGCCCUUUUUCCUAUUUUUCAUUCAUUCAUUCAUUCAUUCAUUUACUCAUUCAUUCCUUCACUUAAACUUUUUUUUUUGUAUCCACUGUAUGCCCAGGACUGCACGAGGCACUGAGUACUUAGAAAUAGUCUCCUGCCAAAAGUCCAAGUUGCUUGGCUGGUUUCCCUCUAUUCAGAAGGUGAUGACAUCAGUGAGGAUAUAAAGUAGCAAGAAUCACGAGGUAGAUGGCCUGGGUCCAGAUCUCAGUGGUGGUCAGAAAUCAAACAGACCAGCUACACUCAGGGAGUUUCCACCCCUCUACCACAGAGAAGUGACGCCUUCAUGCCUUCUUUUGCAAGGUUGAAUUGUGCCAAAACUUUCUUUUGUAGUCCAGCAUCAAUAGGACUGCCGGUCCCUGUCAGAUGACCUCCAAGCUCCUUCCGCUCUUACUACACUGUGGGCUGUGAUUGAUGGAGGAGGGUUUACAAACGUGGAGGCCUCCAGAGCCAGGCAGAGAAGAGCAAGUUAGUACCUUGUACCAAAACAUCAACCUUGUGGAGCCAAGAUUAAUUCAGCCAUAUGAACAUGUUAUAAAGAACUUCAUCCGUGAGAUCAGACUUCAAAGCACAGAAAUGGAAAAUUUGGCCAUUGCGGUGAAGAGAGCCCAGGACAAGGCAGCUAUGCAGUUGAGUGAGUUGGAAGAGGAAAUGGAUCAGAGGAUUCAGGCUGCAGAACAUAAGACACGGAAAGACGAAAAACGCAAAGCUGAGGAAGCCCUCAGUGACCUCAGACGUCAGUAUGAAACUGAAGUAGGAGAUCUGCAGGUGACCAUUAAAAAGCUAAGAAAGCUCGAAGAACAAUCAAAACGCGUAAGUCAAAAGGAAGAUGUGGCUGCAUUGAAAAAACAAAUUUAUGAUUUAUCAAUGGAAAACCAGAAAGUUAAGAAAGACCUUUUAGAAGCACAGACAAACAUAGCCUUUCUUCAGAGUGAGUUAGAUGCUUUGAAAAGUGAUUAUGCUGAUCAGAGUCUGAAUACUGAAAGGGAUCUGGAAAUAAUCCGAGCAUACACAGAAGAUCGAAAUAGUCUUGAGAGGCAAAUUGAAAUACUCCAAACAGCUAACCGGAAGCUACAUGACAGUAAUGAUGGCCUUAGAAGUGCCCUUGAAAACAGUUAUAGCAAGUUCAACAGAUCUUUGCAUAUAAAUAAUAUCUCACCAGGGAAUACAAUUUCUAGAAGCAGUCCCAAAUUCAUUGGUCAUUCCCCUCAACCUCUAGGCUAUGACAGGUCAUCCCGCUCUUCCUAUGUGGAUGAGGACUGUGACUCCCUGGCCCUCUGUGAUCCUCUGCAGAGGACAAAUUGUGAAGUUGACAGCCUGCCUGAAAGCUGCUUCGACAGCGGCUUGUCUACCUUGAGAGAUCCCAAUGAGUAUGACUCAGAAGUGGAAUACAAGCACCAGAGGGGAUUUCAGAGGUCACACGGGGUGCAGGAGAGCUUUGGAGGUGAUGCUUCAGACACAGAUGUUCCUGACAUAAGGGAUGAAGAGACAUUUGGUUUAGAAGAUGUGGCUUCCGUCUUAGACUGGAAGCCCCAAGGGUCUGUUAGUGAAGGCAGCAUUGUUAGUUCAUCAAGAAAGCCCAUCUCAGCACUCUCGCCCCAGACAGACCUGGUAGAUGACAACGCUAAAUCUUUUAGCUCACAGAAGGCUUACAAGAUUGUACUUGCUGGGGACGCUGCAGUGGGGAAGUCUAGUUUCCUCAUGAGACUUUGCAAGAAUGAAUUUCGAGAAAAUAUAAGCGCCACCCUGGGAGUUGAUUUCCAAAUGAAAACCCUCAUUGUGGAUGGAGAACGAACAGUUCUGCAGCUCUGGGAUACAGCUGGUCAGGAGAGAUUCAGAAGUAUUGCCAAGUCUUACUUCAGAAAGGCAGAUGGUGUUUUGCUGCUGUAUGAUGUUACAUGUGAGAAAAGCUUUCUUAACAUACGAGAAUGGGUAGAUAUGAUUGAGGAUGCAGCCCAUGAGACUGUUCCCAUUAUGCUGGUAGGAAACAAGGCUGACAUUCGUGACACUGCUGCUACAGAGGGACAAAAAUGUGUCCCAGGGCACUUUGGAGAGAAACUGGCCAUGACGUAUGGGGCAUUAUUCUGUGAAACAAGUGCCAAAGAUGGUUCUAACAUAGUGGAGGCUGUUCUGCACCUUGCUCGAGAAGUGAAAAAGAGAACUGACAAGGAUGACAGCAGAUCCAUUACCAAUCUAACCGGGACCAAUUCCAAAAAGUCACCACAGAUGAAGAAUUGUUGCAAUGGCUAAAUCCCAAACAUCCUUGGCCUGUGAAGUCUUCAUUUCCAGAAUACUGAAUUUGUGUGACUUAUUUGGCUCUUAACAGAGUGGCACAUCCUACUGACACUGUCCUAUGGAGAGUUACAGUGCAGGAAACCUGAACCCAGCUCUCAGGUCCCUCUGGAACUUUGGCUCUUCUUUGUUUUGUCUCAGUGAGUGAUUUGGGCCCUCUGGCUAAAUAGACUAGUCAUGUCCUUACAGGUCUUAAAAGAUAACAUGUAAAUGUUUUUAAAAUGGUAAAAAAAAAGAAAAGAAAAGAAAUCACAUGCUCAGAUCAAAGCUGUAGAGGAAACUGACAUAAUUAGAUUCAUGUGGUAGCUGAAUUAGGUUACCCACAAAGUCAGCAUUUAAAUAUUUGAUACUAAAGUUCUAGUAAGAAGGGAUUCUCAUCCUAGCUUUGCUGUUAACUGGCCUUGUGACCUUGGACAUGUCACAAGCCCAUGUCGGAUCUGUUUCUUCAUCUGUAAAAUGUGCAGCUUGCCCUCAAAGGCCUUGCAGCCCUUGGCACCUCAGAUUCUGUGGGAAGCAGUAGGACAGAGAGUGUGGUGGCCCACAGUUAAUAAUAGAACUAUGGUUAUUCCUGCUUUUUAAUAUUGGAGUAUUGAUUUUUCUCACUUCUGAAAUAAGGACAGAAUUUGAUUAAAAAAUGGAAACAGAAAUAUCUAUUUUUUAUGUAUAAAGAAACAUGUUUGAGACAAAAAUAGUUGUAUAUAAAAGGAUAUUUCAUAAUCUCAGAAUAGUUACAAAGCUCACUGCUUGAAUUUGGUGUUAAAAAUUCUAAUGGAAACAUGUAAAGCCACAUACUACUGAAAGCACAAUGCCCAGGAAAGUUGUCACUCUUCACUUAAGGGAGUGGUUGCCAGGGGCUGAGAAAGGGAGGAUGGGGAGUGACUGCUAAUAGGUAUGUGGUUUCUUUGGGCGAUGAUGAGAAUGUUCUGGAAUUGGAAUAGUGGUGAUAGUUGUAUAACUGUUUGAAUGUACUAGGAACCACUGAAUUGUAUACUUUGAAAGGGUGAAUUUUAUGGUUGUGAAUUAUCUCACUAAAAAAAAUGCUAGUACUUAGAGUGAUGUAACAUUUUGCAAAAUUUUCAUUUUCGUAUCCCUGCUGAUUUCAAACCUUCCCAUGGUUUAGAAGCAUAACCUGUAAUGUAAUGCAAGUCCCCUAACUCCCUGGUUGCUAACAUUAACUUCCUUAAGUAAUAAUCAAUGAAAGAAAUUCUAUGCAUGGUUUUGAAAUAAUAUCCUUGAAAGAGGAAUCACCAUUAGGAAAGGUGAGUCAGGGUCCUUUGUUUAAUGUGACUAGUGGCUCAUCAUCACCAGUGACCUGGUUGGGCCUACUCUCCUUCCAGAACCUGCAUUGCUUCCCAGACCUCCCCACUGAGAUGCCUCUAAGAGCCAAAGGAGUCAACACUUGAGCCUAGGGUGGGCUACAACAAAAGAUUCUAAUUUACCUUGCUUCAUCUAGGUCCAGGCCCCAAGUAGCUUGCUGAAGGAACUUAAAAAGUAGCUGUUAUUUAUUGUAUUGUAUAAGCUAAAAACAUUUAUUUUUGUUGAAUCGAAACAAUUCCAUGUAGCAAUCUUUUUUCUGUUCACGGUGUUUGUGAUAGAACCUUAAAUUCCGCAAGCAUCAGUUUUUUGAAAAAAUGGGAAUUGACCGGAUAGUUACAGGCAAAGAUUAUAAAUAGCUACAACAUCAUUUAACUUUUAUAAACAUGCCUUCUCUCUAUUGAAGACAUCUGAUAUUUUUGCUGGAAAGUUGGAUCUAUCCUCAGUAACUCUGCCAUGAAUUCCUGUUUCCUGGUUCCAGAAAAAGAAAAGAUUACAUUUCUGAUCAUAAAGAAUGUCUUGCAUAUGGGAAAUUUUUCAAAAUAAGGGGGGUAUUAUUUAUGUGGCAUGGGAAAACUUUUGCCAUGGCUGUUUGUCUUAGUGGCAUCUUUUGAUGACAUUGGAUCAGAUAUAUGUAGAUGCUGAUAUAUGGGACACAUGUUUAGGUUUUGGUGCAGUUGCACAAAACUGUGUUAGUUUAUAUGUUACUGUGUUGCCUUUAUUUAUUCUCUCCAAAGUGUCUCUUUAUAUUUGUUUUACAAUCUGUGAAAGAGUAUACCAUAAUACAGAAGUAUUUUCAUAGUCUUUACCUCUGGAUUGUCCUGUCAGUAUAGCCACGUUGAUGAGAUUACACCAGUGCCUUUGAUGGUCAACCAAUCAUCUUUAAGUAUUUGAGCCCUGAUAAAUAUUUUGGUAACAUAAUCCAAAUUAGAGACUUAGAGCUCUGGUUAGCAAUCAUGUUUAAAGAGAAGCUUCUUAAAGCUCUGUAUGCUGGGAGAUUCAUGAUUAUUACCAACGUUUUGAUUUCAUGAAGGUGUUCUCAAAUUUAAAGCACAUUUUCAGUAAGAACAAAAAUAUUUAAUGUUUUUAUCUUAGACUUGAUACAUUUGCAUAUUACUAUGGAAGUUAUUCACCUUGUCCCUGUUUUUCUUUAAGAUAUUUUAAAAUCAUAGUUAUACUACAGUCCUUUUUUAAAUGUAUCCUGAUACAUUGUAAAAUAUUUUAAUUUCAUUGUGGAAAAUAAUGUUGGAUAAGGAGAUAUUUUUCACUGUUAACUUUUAGCCCAUGCAUUUUCAUAAUUUAUUUUUUUCACUUGCUGCUUUAUAUGACAUAUGUGACAUUUGAUUAUUUAACACUUGAUGUGAUCUGCAUAAACCCAAGUUGCACAACCCUCCUGCUGAAGAUAAAAUUGAGGUUAAAGAUAAAGAUUUAUUUUCAUAUUUGUACAGUGAUCGGCUUCAGUGAUGGUUUUUGUGGGCAUUUAUUGUGUGUGUGUAAGAAAUUUCAUAUGUAUAUAUUAAGUAGGCCUCUGAGUAUUGAAUAAUUGUUUUAUGAUUUUGAUUUAUAUGGUUUACAUUUUCAUUGUGUGGGCCAUAUUUCGUUUAUACUGUUUAUUUCUCUUCAAACCUUAAUAAUUAUACCAUAAAGUGUAAUUUUUAUAGCAAUGCAAAUGUCUAAGGAACUACAAAUAUUUUCUACGUUGUAAAUUCAAUAAAGCUUGCUUCCUUUGGC